AGGCGGAGUCUUGCUAUGUACAGUGGUGCAGUCUUGGCUCACUGCAAACUCCCCCUCCCGGGUUCAAGUUCUCCUGCCUCAGCCUCCUGAGUAGCAGGGAUUACAGGCACCUGACUAAUUUUUAUAUUUUUAGCAGAGAGAAGGUUUCACCAUGUUGUCCAGGCUGGUCUGGAACUCCUGACCUCAAGUGAUCUGCCCACCUUGGCCUCCCAAAAUGCUGGGAUUACAGGCAUGAGCCACCAUGCCCAGCAGACACUGCUCUCUUUGAAGGCAUCUUAGAAAGUGUCCUAGGCCCAUAGACACAUAUAAGCCUACUGUUAAGAUGGCAGAGAGGCAGAGUAAUGGAAGAGUCUGUAGACUUGGUAUUGGAACAGCCAGUUAAAUUCCUUUACUUUGCUUAUUGCAGCUUGGUGACCUGAUUCCACAUACCACCUAACUUUCUCAGUUUAGUUUUCCUAGUUUGAAAAAUGAAAGUGCCUUGUAAACUAAUGUGUUACACAAAUGUCUGCAUUAUUUACUUUUACCAUUGCUAAUCAUAAAUUUUUUAAUCUUGAUUUUAUUAGUUUUACUUUUGACUUUAUUCCCUUUUAAGAUAGUCUGGUUACUGGGAGCCACAGUUAGAAUGACUCACCCAGUAAUUCCCUAGUCUUUAAGCCAAAACCAUUUCCUAUAUAUGGAGUUCUGGCAUUUUUGCAAAUGUGCUUUAUGGUACCCUUGAGGAUGGUCUCUGGAUGUUUCCCGAUUUCAAACUUGUAUGAAAGAUUAGACCAGGGAAUUUCUUUGUGUAGAAAUUUUCUCAUAGUUGUCUUAAGUUUUAACUCAUGUACAUUAAUCUUUAGCUUUGCUUUACAUUUGUUUUCUGUUGAUAGCCAAGUCAUUGCUUGUUAAAUAUUCCUUAGAAAUGAACUUUCCUAUCAAUUUAAAAUUAUUUUAGCUGUAUCUGUGGCACUUUUUUUUUUUCUCUUUUGAGAUGGAGUCUCGCUCUGUUGCCCAGGCUGGAGUGCAGUGGUGUGGUCUUGGCUCACUGCAACCUCCACUUCCCGGGUUCAAGCCAUUCUCCUGCCUCAGCCUCCCGAGUGGCUGGGAUUAGAGACGCCUGCCACCACACCUGGCUAAUAUUUUGUAUUUUUAGUAGAGAGGGGUUUCAUCAUGUUGGCCAGGCUGGUCUCGAACUCCUGACCUCAGGUGAUCGCCCACCUUAGCCUCCCAAAGUGCUGGGAUUAUAGGUGUGAGCCGCCGCACCCAGCCUGUGGUACCUUUUAAAAAGUAAAAAAUUCAAUGGCGUGAAACAACAGAAGGAGUUCUGCUUCCAUUUCUAGUUGUUAAACGCCUUUCUCUAGCCAAGAUCACAUAUAUUUCUGGUUUUUUAUAGCUAGUGCACUAUAACUCUGACAGUCAUGGUUAGAUUGAUAGUUUUACUGAAAGUAAUUUAUCAAAAUCCCCAUUAGAUUGUCUUUUAAUGUCAACAUAUUAAACCUGUUCCCUGAGAGAUACUUUCCUAUUUGUUCUCCUUGCCCUUUAAAUAUCAUUUGGUGCCAGUGAGAUGAAGAAUAGAAAAUGUAUAUCUUUUAGGGGAACUUCGCAAGCCUGAGAUCCCCCACUACAUAUAGUCAUUCAGAAAAUGUUUCUUAAGCACUUACUACCUACUUUUUCUCAGACAUUGUACCGGGACAUAUAGAUUAAAAGAAAGAGUCUUUAGUCUCAAGGAUUUUACAGUCUAAUGGGGAAGCAGAUGUGUACAAAUAUAAAUGAUGCAAUACAGAAAUUAUUGUGGCAUGGUAUACAGGGAGAAAUGAAAGCAUUGAAGAAGGCAAAGAAGUCUUCCUCGGGAAGUCAUGGCUUCAAAGAGAAAAGUAGGCUGUGUCUUAAAGGAUAAGUAUGACUUUGCCAAGCUAAUUUAGGGAACUUUGUAUUCUAGGAAGAGGGAACAGAAUGUGCAAAGCCUCGAAGGUGCACUGUUUUGUGUGUGUGUGUGUGCGUGUGGGGAUUCUUUAGUAUAUUUUGACUGCAUGUUGAGGAGUGAUGAGGAGUAGAGUUUGACAGGUAGUCAGGAUACUGUAAGGUUAAAACCUGAGCUCUGUGGUUGACUUGCUUCGUGGCAUUGAGAUUUUGAAUAUGCACUGUGCUUUAGACUUCCUGUUGUGUAAGAAGCCCAUAGUAUUGUAGGUCCACCUGCUAUUCACAUGGGGUUAUAAAUAUUGCAGGCAUGAAACGCUUCCUGAUCGCUGAAUAGUAAGAAAGGUCUGAGCAUGGUGCCGAUUAAAUUCUCCAUUGAAAUGUACCUUUGUGGGUACAUUAAAUUAUUUUAGCAUAAGUCUAGUGAAGUGCCAGCAGUAGAUACUAUGUUAUUUCUGGAGCUCUUGAUGUUGAUUUUUGAGGCUGAACAUGCUCUUAGCCUCAAGCAGGUCAUAUUUGGAAUACCUGAUGUGUGCUCCUGGUUGCUCAGUGCUUAGGAUGCAUAAACAGGUAGCUGCAGUCUCAUCUCUCAGUAUAUAUACUUUUCAGCAAAUCUUUUUUUUCUAGAUAAAUUGGAAAACUACCUUUUUUCUGCAUUUUUCAUCUGAUGUCAUUAUGGUAUGUAGGUGGCAGCUUUCUUGGGCACAGUUGUCUAUAUAACUGUUCAUCACAUGAGUCAUUGUCUGUUUCUGUUCUUCUGCCUGAAAAUUCCAUCUUGGAAAUCGUGUCAUGCAAUCGGUGACUGCGACAUUCUACUUGUUAUGUACACUGCCACUGGCUUUGUAUGUUAUGUUGAUGGACUCUACCUGUGCUACAGUGAAGGGAUAAAGUGACUUAUUAAAUUGAGUCAGACUCAGUUCCUCCAAAUGGUAUUUCCUGUAAAAAUGAUGCCAAGCAAGAUUCUGCAUAAAACAUGCAUAUGCUUUACACUGUAAGCAUACAGUGCCUACCUUUUGUUAUUGUGUCUGCUUAAAUCCUUACCACAGUUGUACUCCUGUUUGAUCAAGUGGCCAGUUUAACUAGAUACUAGCUUUGAAGAAGUUCUGUAUUGGCCCCUGGAAUGUGACAGUUCAUACCACAUUGAAAAGGCUUUGUGAAUGCCGGUCCACUGAUGGCUGAACUGCAGGUCUCUCCCCAGUGGAAAGCCCCAGAGAUGAGCCAGAUCUGCCUCAGCUGUGGCCAUCCGUCAGCGGCACUGUGAGGUGAAUGCUAUUGUACACGUUUUAUAGAUGAGGAAACUAAGGCUCAGGAAAUGGCCGCGAUGGGCCUCUUGGAACAUUGGUGUGUUCAUCUGCAUUCGAUGUGCUGGAAUCCACAGGAAUCUGGGGGUGCACAUAUCCAGGGUAAAGUCAGUUAACCUCGACCAGUGGACUCAAGAACAGAUUCAGUGCAUGCAAGAGAUGGGAAAUGGAAAGGCAAACCGACUUUAUGAAGCCUAUCUUCCUGAGACCUUUCGGCGACCUCAGAUAGACCCAGCUGUUGAAGGAUUUAUUCGAGACAAAUAUGAGAAGAAGAAAUACAUGGACCGAAGUCUGGACAUCAAUGCCUUUAGGAAAGAAAAAGAUGACAAGUGGAAAAGAGGGAGCGAACCAGUUCCAGAAAAAAAAUUGGAACCUGUUGUUUUUGAGAAGGUGAAAAUGCCACAGAAAAAAGAAGACCCACAGCUACCUCGGAAAAGCUCCCCGAAAUCCACAGCGCCUGUCAUGGAUUUGUUGGGCCUUGAUGCUCCUGUGGCCUGCUCCAUUGCAAAUAGUAAGACCAGCAAUACCCUAGAGAAGGAUUUAGAUCUGUUGGCCUCUGUUCCAUCCCCUUCUUCUUCCGGUUCCAGAAAGGUUGUAGGUUCCAUGCCAACUGCAGGGAGUGCCGGCUCUGUUCCUGAAAAUCUGAACCUGUUUCCGGAGCCAGGGAGCAAAUCAGAAGAAAUAGGCAAGAAACAGCUCUCUAAAGACUCCAUUCUUUCACUGUAUGGAUCCCAGACGCCUCAAAUGCCUACUCAAGCAAUGUUCAUGGCUCCCGCUCAGAUGGCAUAUCCCACAGCCUACCCCAGCUUCCCCGGGGUUACACCUCCUAACAGCAUAAUGGGGAGCAUGAUGCCUCCACCAGUAGGCAUGGUUGCUCAGCCAGGAGCUUCUGGGAUGGUUGCCCCCAUGGCCAUGCCUGCAGGCUAUAUGGGUGGCAUGCAGGCAUCAAUGAUGGGUGUGCCGAAUGGAAUGAUGACCACCCAGCAGGCUGGCUACAUGGCAGGCAUGGCAGCUAUGCCCCAGACUGUGUAUGGGGUCCAGCCAGCUCAGCAGCUGCAAUGGAACCUUACUCAGAUGACCCAGCAGAUGGCUGGGAUGAACUUCUAUGGAGCCAAUGGCAUGAUGAACUAUGGACAGUCAAUGAGUGGCGGAAAUGGACAGGCAGCAAAUCAGACUCUCAGUCCUCAGAUGUGGAAAUAAAAACAAAACACCUGUAUGGCUGCCAUUCUCUUCAGCCCUCGCUCUCCCCUUUCCACAGCCUCCACCCCUGACCCCCAUCCUCUUUUCCUACCUCUCUGUUUGGUUUAGAAAUUGCUCAAUAAGUCAUUUGGGGUUUGGCAUCCUGCCCAGCCACUUCCCAAACAUGAAGACCUCUCUGUUGCUUUAUGUUGUACAUGCCCCAUAGCCAUCCCAACGUCCUCCCCAGUCCUCUCCUGGCACCAGCACCUUAGAAGUUGUUGGCAGAAGGCACUUAAACUGUGGGAGAAGUGUGCACACCUUUGAGUCCCUUCCCUCAAGGUUAAAGCUCCUGUCAGACUCUCAGAAGGGUCUGUGGGUGUUGUAUAUUAGGCAAACAGGGGAAAGCUUAGAGGUCCUUCUAUAUGUGUUAAUAAGCUGUUUCUAAGUGUUUAAAUUUGAAAAGCAUCAUGUUCUCAUGAUUUAUGGGAAUGAAGCAAGUACUGAAAUCAAAUUAAAUACUCCCUGGGUCCUGGGUCAGUUUGACCCUAGCCCUGGGGUGAGGCAAGCCCCCUCCUAUGAGGAUGAGCAAAAAUACUACUCUCUUCGCCCUGAGUUGCUUUCUGGAUCUGGGGCUUCAGGACUUGCUGCUUCAGUCAGCCUUUAUUAGCACCAAAGACUUUAUGAAGAUCCCACACACAGACACACAUCCCUUCCCGCCUCCCCCCUGCCUUCAGUAGGAUCUGGCUCCGUGGCUGGAGGACCAACCCCUAUAGUGGGAAUGCAGAGCUUAACGUGUACUGCUUGUGUGUGUGCGUGAGUGUGUGUGUGUGUAUGAGUGUGUGUUCCGCCUCCCACCCUCUCCCCAUCUGCUCUGGGUAUUUUUGUUUUUGUUUAGUUUUAGGUUUACAACAGAGAGGAAUUAAUUUAUCAGCAGCCUAAAACUGUUGUGUUUUUCUUAUGGUUUAAAAAACGCCAUGUCAUUGAUAACUCCCUUUCUCCCUUCCCUUCUCCCGGUCUGCUGAUCACUCUUUCAUGCCUGUGUAUCCAGGGUGCUCUGUUUCCCCACCGUUCCCAGGUGUACGAGGCAGAGGGCCGGGACAGCUUUCCUCUCAGUCAUUGUUCACCCCACUUGAAAAUUCAGACAAGAAAACUUUGCUUAAAAGAUUUCAUGUGUGGGAACCACAGUUCCUGGCUGCCUUUCUCCUGUGUAUGUGUAAAUUCCUUAAUAAAUAUUGCAGGGAAGGAC